AGUACGGCGGGAGGCACUAGAGGGAGCUGCGGCCGCUCCGGCCCGGCCCCGAGCACCGCCUCCCCAGCCAGCGCCGCCGCGAUGGCGGAGGACAGCGAGUCUGCGGCCAGCCAGCAGAGCCUGGAACUGGACGACCAGGACACGUGCGGGAUAGACGGGGACAAUGAGGAGGAGACGGAGCACGCCAAAGGUUCAAGGUCAGCCCAAAUGUCCUUUCUUUCAUGAAGCCUUCCGCAGCCACUAUGACCAAAGGCGCUGACCCCUGCCGGAAGCCCUGUAGCUCUUAGUGAGUGUAUCUUUCCCGUGACAUCUUUCCCAGUUGCUCUCACCUCAUCUCCCCAGCCCUCUGCUCGGGAAGACCCUCAUUCUCCUGCCCCAAGCUGUGGCUCCUAGAGAAGUCCUGGAGGGUAUUUGGGAGCCAAAAAGAAAAAGAAGAAACAGAAGAGAAAAAAGGAGAAACCAAAUUCCGGAGGCACCAAGUCAGACUCGGCAUCUGAUUCCCAGGAGAUUAAAAUUCAGCAGCCUUCGAAACACAACACCAUCUGGCAGCAGAUUUCAGCGGGAGCAGCCAUGGAAUCCCAGUGUUCCAAUGCAGAAGUUGCAGGAUAUCCAGAGAGCAAUGGAGCUGCUAUCCGCAUGCCAGGGCCCAGCCAGGAACAUUGAUGAGGCUGCAAAGCACAGAUACCAGUUUUGGGACACACAACCGGUACCAAAACUAGAUGAAGUCAUAACAUCUCAUGGUGCAAUUGAACCAGAUAAAGACAACGUACGCCAAGAACCGUAUUCUUUGCCACAGGGUUUUAUGUGGGACACUUUAGACUUGAGUGAUGCCGAAGUGCUCAAGGAGUUAUACACGUUGUUAAAUGAGAAUUACGUAGAAGAUGAUGACAAUAUGUUCCGAUUUGACUAUUCACCCGAGUUCCUGUUGUGGGCUCUGCGUCCACCAGGCUGGCUCCUGCAGUGGCACUGUGGGGUCAGAGUGUCUUCAAAUAAAAAACUGGUCGGGUUCAUAAGUGCCAUCCCAGCAAACAUUCGGAUUUAUGACAGUGUGAAGAAGAUGGUAGAAAUCAACUUUCUUUGUGUUCAUAAGAAGUUGAGAUCGAAACGGGUAGCCCCAGUGCUAAUCCGAGAGAUCACUAGAAGAGUGAACCUGGAAGGGAUCUUCCAGGCUGUGUACACCGCGGGAGUGGUUCUUCCUAAGCCCAUAGCCACAUGCAGAUACUGGCAUCGAUCACUAAACCCCAGAAAAUUGGUAGAAGUGAAAUUUUCUCACUUGAGUAGAAAUAUGACUUUACAGAGAACAAUGAAGCUAUACAGACUUCCAGAUGUUACAAAGACUUCAGGUUUGAGACCAAUGGAACCAAAAGAUAUCAAAUCAGUUCGAGAAUUAAUCAACACUUACCUGAAGCAGUUUCAUCUGGCUCCAGUGAUGGAUGAAGAGGAAGUAGCCCACUGGUUCCUCCCCCGGGAGCACAUUAUUGACACGUUUGUAGUGGAGAGCCCCAACGGUAAACUGACUGAUUUCCUGAGCUUCUAUACGCUCCCCUCCACGGUGAUGCACCACCCUGCUCACAAGAGCCUCAAAGCCGCCUACUCAUUCUACAACAUCCACACAGAGACGCCCCUGCUGGACCUCAUGAGCGACGCGCUCAUCCUGGCUAAAUCGAAAGGAUUUGAUGUAUUCAAUGCACUGGAUUUGAUGGAAAAUAAGACAUUCUUGGAAAAACUCAAGUUUGGUAUAGGAGAUGGCAAUUUGCAGUAUUACCUGUACAAUUGGAGGUGUCCAGGUACAGAUUCUGAAAAGGUUGGACUAGUACUACAAUAGAUGGAUAUUUUUAUUUCUAGAACUCUGACAUCAUCAUUUGUUAAUAUUUAAUGAUUUCUGGAACUGCCAUUCCAAAGAAGAAUAAAAGCACAACUCAAGUGAAAUUGAAGUAGUCGAUAAUCAGAAAAGAUGACAAAAGUCCACAUGUGACAUUUGUACGUUUCUAGCUAGAAUGUUAAACUUCAUCCUUUUUUUACUGUUGACCUAUUUGUGGGAGGGAUGAAAGGCUACAAAGAGCACAUUCUUGUAAUUUUCAAAUUUUUGCCUGUCUCUUGAAGAGGUAUUUUUUCACCCUUAGAAAAGGGACUGUUUUUCUAUGGACUAAGUAGAAGUUACAGAGUCAUGUAAGAAAAUCUUUGCUAUUGUGUGGAGAGAAAUUGCUGCAUUUCUGUUUCUUAAGUGAUGGUACAUUUGUCCAUGUAACAGAACAAAAGAUCCAUUUGGAAAUUUUUUUUACUGGUAUCACCUUACAUGGUAUCACUGGGAACAUUUAUGGAAUCAACACUUCUGUAGCUCAGUGACAGGUGGUGGUUGUUUAAGUGCAGAGCAAUAUUAAAAUGUACUGGUGACUAGUACAUGUAUUUCUCCAUAAGCAGAGUUGCCGAAUCAAUAAACAUGCAAGUUUGUACUUUGAUCUUUACCAGGUCAGUGGAUUGCUUCAAAAGCAGAGUUUUGUGCAAGCACUCACUGUGCUCUCUGAAAGAGCCUGAGGCCGGGCGUGGUGGCUCACGCCUGUAAUCCCAGCACUUUGGGAGGCCAAGGUGGGCAGAUCAUGAGGUCAGGAGAUCGAGACCAUUCUGGCCAACAUAGUGAAACCCCAUCUCUACUAAAAAUACAAAAAUUAGCCGGGCGUGGUGGCGUGUGCCUGUAGUCCCAGCUGCUUGGGAGGCUGAGGCAGGAGAAUCGCUUGAACCUGAGAGGUGAGGUUGCAGUGAGCCGAGAUCGAGCCACUGCACUCCAGCCUGGGUGACAGAGCGUGAGACUCCGUCUCAAAAAAAAAAAAAAAGAAAGAGCCUGUACCCGCGACUAACUAGACUUUUCUGCUGUUGUGCAAAGUUCAGUUUCUUCUCAGCAACAUCAAGGAUAUAUGAAGAAAAGGAAAUAAAAAACUGUAAAGUCAAAAGAGAUGCCUGGUGGAACUUAUUCGUGCUAUCAGGGCAUUGAUAGUUUGAAUGUUUUUAUUACUUAUGCAAAAUUGCACAUACUCCUCUAUGCUGAUUUUAUCAUGAAAACUGUCAUGUGUCAUGCUAAUGGAAAAUGUCUUAUUUGUAAAUAAGUAUUCAUAAUUUUGUUACUGAUGGUGUUUUUAAUCUAGAAUUUGAAAAACUUUCAUGGCUUACAGAUGUGUGUUUAUAUUGCCAAUAAUCUGCGGGAAAAAUAAGAUGCUAACCGAGGCCACGUAGCCUGGCCUCAACUCAGAUACCACAAAGUAGAUGCCUUGGCUGGGUGUGGUGGCUCACGCCUGUAAUCCCAGCACUUUGGGAGGCCAAGGCGGGCGAAACAUUUGAGGUCAGGGGUUCGAGACCAGCCUGGCCAACAUGGUGAAACCCCAUCUCUACUAAAAAUUCAAAAAGAACUAGCUGGGUGUGGUGGCGGGUGCCUGUAAUCCCAGCUGCUAGGAGGCUGAGGCAGGAGAAUCACUUGAACCCAGGAGGCGGAAGUUGCAGUGAGCCAAGAUCGUGCCACUGCACUCCAGCCUGGGUGACAGUGCAAGACUCCGUCUCAAAAAACAAAAGUAGAUACUUUUCCCUGCUUUUACUGGGCCAGUGCCUAGGAAGUUCAGUGCAGAAGUUAAUUGUUUUAGACAUGAUGGCAUUUCCUUCAAGUUAUGAGUCCAGUGAAACCAAUCAUAUCUUAUCCCAGGCAGGGGCCACCAAACUAUGGCCUGUGGGCUAAAUCCAGCCCAUUGCUUAUUUUUGUGUAGCCCACAGGCUAAGAAUGUUUUUAUUUUCUGGAAUGGUUGAGGAGAAAAAGCCAAAAAAUGACAUCAUUUUGUGACAUGUGCAAAUUACACAAAAUUCAAAUUCCGGUGUCCCUCAAUAAGGUUUUAUUGGAACAUAGCCAUACUUUUUUUUUUUUUUUUUUUAGGACAGGGUCUCACUCUAUUGUCCAGGCUAGAAUACAGUGGCACAGUCAACAGCUCACUGCAGCCCCAAACUCCUGGGUUAAAAUGAUCCUCCUGCUUCAGCGUCUUUUUGAAGAAAAAGAACUAGCUGGGCGUGCAUACCACCACGCCUGGCUAAGUUUUUCAUUUUUUGUAGAGACAAGGUCUUGCUAUGUUUCCCGUGCUGGUCUUUAACUCCUGGCCUCAAGUGAUCCUUCUGCCUUGGCCUCCCAAAGUACUGGGAUUAUAGACAUGAGCCACCACUCUUGGCCACAGCCACUUUCAUUUACAUAUUGCCUAUGGCUGCUUCACACUACAAAGCUGAGUUGAGUUGUUGUGACAGAUUGUGUGGCCUGCAAAGCCUAAGAUAUUCACUCUCUGGUCUUUUACAGAAAGUUUGUUGACCUUGGUCACUACGAAGGAGUUGGAACUCUCCUUUCUAUAGGUUGCCGUGAUUCUAAAGACCAACCCACAGCUGUGACAUCCCUGAGACUACCACCAGAGGGCGACUGGGCCCCACAGUAGUACAUAAUAUAGGACCUCUCUUGGAGAUAAUGGAAGACUUGGAAUUUCAGAUGGUUCCACCCUAAUUGCAUUAGCGUUCUUUCUUAACAGGAGAAAGGCUUCAAGAAACAAAACAGUCCUCAUUCACUGGAACAGGGUUUGAGAUACCAGCAUUAAGUAAAUGAGAUUUUGACUUAACCUGGAGUCAAGGCUCUAAUUUAGGACUUUACUUCCCACUCAUUUUCAUGCCACAAAGUCUAUACAAAGUAGGUUUUCAAAUAAUUGCAGAAUCAGCCAGGCACGGUGGCUCACACCUGUAAUCCCUGCACUUUGGGAGGCCAAGGUGAGCAGAUCACUUGAGGUCAGGAGUCUUGAGACCAGCCUGGCCAACAUGGUGAAGCCCUAUCUCUACUAAAAUUACAAAAACUAGCCGGACAUGGGGGUGUGCACCUGUAAUCCCAGCUAUUCAGGAGGCUGAGGCAGGAGAAUCGCUUGAACCCAGGAGGCGGGGUUGCAGUGAGCCGGGAUCACACCACUGCACUCCAGCCUGGGCAACAGAGUGAGACUCUAUCUCGAAAGUAAAAUAAAUAACUGCAGCAUUGCCAGUUGGAAACUUUGUCAUGAGCUUACCUCACGGUGACAGUUACACUGCUCCUUUAAAGAGUCAUUUACAUAAUUUGUUAUCAAAUUAUUAACCACUUUUAAAUAGAAUAAUAACUACAUUUGCCUCCAUAAUUGAAGCAGAUUACUAAUUAACAUUUUCGAGAAUUAAACUGCUUGCUUAUGAAGUAGCUAUUAAAACUAAAUUGAAAUGCAA